ACUCGCAGCUGCCGGGUGUUGGGGAAAGAGUCGCCUGCCUCCGGACUGGAGUGCAGACCUCUGACCCUGGAGUCGCUCGGCCGCUGGGAACCGUCCCCUUGGGUCGUCGCCUGGGCCGCCCGUCGUUCCCCGGCCCCGAGGGGUCCGGCUGGCCGCGGUGUGGGUAGAGGUCAGCAUGAGCCAAGGGGUCCGCCGGGCAGGCGCUGGGCAGGGGGUAGCGGCCGCGGUGCAGCUGCUGGUCACCCUGAGCUUCCUGCGGAGCGUCGUCGAGGCGCAGGUCACUGGAGUUCUGGAUGAUUGCUUGUGUGAUAUUGACAGCAUCGAUAACUUCAAUACCUACAAAAUCUUCCCCAAAAUAAAAAAAUUGCAAGAGAGAGACUAUUUUCGUUAUUACAAGGUUAAUCUGAAGCGACCUUGUCCUUUCUGGGCAGAAGAUGGCCACUGUUCAAUAAAAGACUGUCAUGUGGAGCCCUGUCCAGAGAGUAAAAUUCCGGUUGGAAUAAAAGCUGGGCAUUCUAAUAAGUACUUGAAAAUGGCAAACAAUACCAAAGAAUUAGAAGAUUGUGAGCAAGCUAAUAAACUGGGAGCAAUUAACAGCACAUUAAGUAAUCAAAGCAAAGAAGCUUUCAUUGACUGGGCAAGAUAUGAUGAUUCACGGGAUCACUUUUGUGAACUUGAUGAUGAGAGAUCUCCAGCUGCUCAGUAUGUAGACCUAUUGCUGAACCCAGAGCGUUACACUGGCUAUAAAGGGACCUCUGCAUGGAGAGUGUGGAACAGCAUCUAUGAAGAGAACUGUUUCAAGCCUCGAUCUGUUUAUCGUCCUUUAAAUCCUCUGGCGCCUAGCCGAGGCGAAGAUGAUGGAGAAUCAUUCUACACAUGGCUAGAAGGUUUGUGUCUGGAGAAAAGAGUCUUCUAUAAGCUUAUAUCGGGACUUCAUGCUAGCAUCAAUUUACAUCUAUGCGCAAAUUAUCUUUUGGAAGAAACCUGGGGUAAGCCCAGUUGGGGACCUAAUAUUAAAGAAUUCAAACACCGCUUUGACCCUGUGGAAACCAAGGGAGAAGGUCCAAGAAGGCUCAAGAAUCUUUACUUUUUAUACUUGAUUGAGCUUCGAGCUUUGUCAAAGGUGGCUCCAUAUUUUGAGCGCUCAAUUGUCGAUCUUUACACUGGAAAUGCAGAAGAAGAUGCUGACACAAAAACUCUUCUACUGAAUAUCUUUCAAGAUACAAAGUCCUUUCCCAUGCACUUUGAUGAGAAAUCCAUGUUUGCAGGUGACAAAAAAGGGGCCAAGUCACUAAAGGAGGAAUUCCGAUUACAUUUCAAGAAUAUCUCCCGUAUAAUGGACUGUGUUGGAUGUGACAAAUGCAGAUUAUGGGGAAAAUUACAGACUCAGGGUUUAGGAACUGCCCUGAAGAUAUUAUUCUCUGAAAAAGAAAUCCAAAAGCUUCCAGAGAAUAGUCCAUCUAAAGGCUUCCAACUCACCCGACAGGAAAUAGUUGCUCUUUUAAAUGCUUUUGGAAGGCUUUCUACAAGUAUAAGAGACUUACAGAAUUUUAAAGUCUUAUUACAACACAGUAGGUAAUAAAGGCUUUUAUGUGUCUAACUAGAGACAUAAAGUGACUGUGGAAAGCCUUUUAAUUAUGGACAUUCAUCAGAAAGACACUAAUCUGACUUCAAGAAUUCUGAACUAUUAAAUAGAAAAUUUAAAUGCUCACUUGAAUAUUUAUGAUUCUUAAUAGAUUAUUAUCAACUAGAGAUAUUUAUAAAUGAAGUAUAUACUUUUAAAACAUGUAAGUUAUACUAAUUUUGUGUUUAAUUUCAUAUGUUUUCAUGUAAUGAAAAUUCUAUUUUUUUUAGAAUUGGUUUUGUUUUUAUUCUAUUAUCCUUUAUUUCCAGUUGUCAAACUUUAAAUGGCUAUGUCUGCAUUCUAAUAACACUGUUCAGUCUGUUAUGGAAAAGGAGAACUAGGGAACAAAUGUUGCUCAGGGCUGGUGUCAGUGAGAAAAAUUUAUCAAUGCUUUUUAAUGUGUUUUUACCCUUGCCUCACUGUGUGUGUGUCACUUUCUAUAAUAUAAAGAAAUACUAUAAUAUUUCUAGAAUCUGGAACUGUCACCAUGAUGAAUGGCCCUUUCAAUGCAUAGUUACAGAAAUUCCUGAAGAUUCCCCAGGACUUCAAUUUCAUUGGUUUUUAUUUGCAGUUUUUAGUUGCUGUAAUUGUUGCUGUUUCCAGUCUAAAGGACCUCCUUUGGUAAAGGUGAACAAGACCUCUCCCCUAUGCUACCCAGCCAGAUUUUGUGUGUGUAAUGGGCUGGCCCAAGAGUGUUCUUUUACUUAGAACUCCUUUUGAUUUUGCUUUUCUCUGCCCCUAGAAAUUUUAGGGACAAAGACAUUUUGGAAAUUGUCAGUUACUUUUAGAAAGAAAACACUGCAGAAAUAUUUAACAGAUUACUUCUUGAUAAAAUUUAAAUGGGAUUAUAUGAAUUUAUAAUGCCAAUUGAAAAUAUUAUAUACACAAAAUUUGCUAUUUUCACUUAAAGUAAGCAUUUUUAAAGGAUUUAUUUUAGAAUACAAUCUAUGCAAUCCUCGAACUCAGUGUGCUUUUCCCUGACAGGAUAUAUAAAAAGGUAGAUUAGGUCAACCCUCCUUUAAGCUUACUCUCCCCUCACCUUUUCUUUUCACUGUAUAUAAACGGUACUUUCUGUGAUUCAUACCAACAGAGGACUUUCUGUGAUUCAUACCAACAGUCCUAAACUGUCAUUUUCUAAAUCUGGGAUUUAAAAUCUUUAGACAAUAUUUAAAAUCUUGAUUUUUUUUAAAUGUCAGCAGAUACAAUUUGGAAGAUUGCAUCUGUGUAGAAGUAAUGCAGGUACAAGAUCUAGAGUUUUUCCUUAGACUCUUUAGUCUUUUCUGAAUUAAAGAAUAAGUGCUCUUAAAUCCAUAUUUUAUCCUGUCAAAGUCUGAAAUGUGUUCAUUGAUGAUUUGGUGACAUCUAAAAAAUUGUAUUUAGUUGGCUUGGCUCACCCCUCUUAAAAAUACUUAGCCAUCUCUUGGUGGGAUGUGGUGGGGGUAUUAAGGUCUCAGAGUUAUUUAUUUUCUCACCUAAUUUCAAACCUUUAUAAACUUGGGGUUUUGUUGUUGAUGGUGGUAGUAUUUUUUGUUAAGUUGUUUAAAAGGCUGACUUGAUUGGAGCCUCCUCUACUUUUUCUUGAGGGUUGCAAGUAUUGUAUGGUGGGGGAGGGGGGCCUUAAGGCAAACUGUCUAAAAAGUGACUAUCCAAUUAAUUUAACUAGUAAAUUAGUAAGAAUUAUUCUUAGUAUUCACUCAGAGUUUAAGAUGUGAAAAAUCUGCACUUUGUUUAUCACUCUAAAUGUAAAGAACUUUUUGAUAGUGUUAUUUCACCACUCCCUCAGUUAAAGGCUAUUAUUUAAACUGUUUACUGGAGAAAAUCCUCGCUCAUGUCCAUUUAUUGUUUUUUUCUGUACUGUGAUUUGUUUCAAGCUUAGGAAAACUAGUAUAUUAGAGUAUGUUCUAGGAAAUUAAAAGAUCUGGUUAGAGUAAAAAGUUCUUUUUAAGGUUCUUAACUAAUUUUUUCACAACUAAGAAAAUAAAUGAAGUAUUCUUAGGCUGAAAUUCAUCUUAUUUUAUCAUAAAUUAGAUUGUAGGGGCAGCCUACAUUUUUGUGUAUGUGUUUUUAUUUCUUAAAUGAUUGUGUGAGCCUGGUGACAUUUUAUGGUUCUUGUGAUCUAAACUGUUUUUCCAAUUCACAUCUUUUGUCGUGAAGUGAUAUUAUACUAGAGUACUGUUUGCAUUGUAAAAAUGCUUUGCUGGUGCUCUGGCAUUUUGUCUUUAUCUCAUCACCUAAUUUAAAAACCCAGCACUUGAUAAUAUAACUGACAGAAAUGAUUGUACCCACUGAUGAAGUAAUGAAAAUGAAGAAAAGGAAAAUAUUCCUUCCUUCAAUGGCGUAAGUUUAUUUUUUACUUAAGUGGCAUCUAUGUAAGUUAGACAAACUAUAUAUUAAAAUUGGUAAACUUUGAAUGUUUCUCCUGUUUUGAUUCUUAGAUUAUGAGGAGGAUCAGACAGAAUAAGACUCCACACUUUUGAAAUUUGAUAAGUCAAAACGUUUUAUUUUGACAUUUUUAACAUUGUGAAUUAUUCGAUAUUUGUAAUCUCUGUAUGUAUAUGAAACUCUGCCAUGUUUUUCAACUUUGCCUAUGUGCCACUGUAUAUAAGAAAGGACAGCUAUUUUGAUCUUCAUCAGCAUUGCCUUCAGCUGAAAAUUUGGGAACAGUUCACAGUAAACCUCUCAGUAGUUUGCAAACUGAGGUACCUGCAGAAACCAUAGCUACUCACCAAAAUACACAGAUUAGGUGCAUGGUAUCGUGGAAAUUAUUUGGUAAAAAAACACACACACAAAUCUAUGUGUACUGUAUUUUAAGGAAUAUCUACAGGUGCAGCUUUGAUUUUGAACAGAAUUCCAAAUAAUUUACUGUUGUACCCACCAGAAUCUAGAAAAUGUGAAUUAAAGUACAUGUUUCUGCAAUCUUUUCUGUCUUGUUUUUCCCCGCUAUUUUAAGUGUUUCUUUUUAUGGCAUGAGAAUUUGAUUGUAACCUGUGGAGAAGGGAGAAAAUGUAUUUAUAAGUAGUCUGAGGUUGUUUCUUAUCAUAAUGGCAAGCAUUGGCUGGCAUUGUAUUAAGGGCUUUUACAUGCAUAGUUUGGCUUUAAAAGAAUACACCGUUAAUCUUCACAAUAGCACUAGUAGGUAGGUACAAUUACUUCUCUGUUUUAUAAGUAAGAAGACUGAGGAUAAAAAAGGCUAAGUAACCUGUCCAUAGUCACAAAUUCUAGGUUGUGGAGCAAGAAUUUGAGACGAGAAAGACUGAUUCUAGAACCUUUGUGACAUUUUGUAAGUUGGCCUAUUUCCAUUCAGCUACAAAGUGGGAACAAUUAAAAGCAUUGUUUGAUUUGUAUUGAAUCAUAAAGCUUAUAAAAUAUG